GGCGGAGAUCCUCGUUGGGGCUGGGAAACUCCUGCAAAACUCGAGACCAGGAAGCCAGCCCGCACCCCAACCCCCACCAAAGCCACCUACUCUUCUUCUGUGGGAGGCCAGUCCACAUCCGCUCUCACCCGAGAGAGAUAUUCAGCUGGAUCCAAAGUGACUGAUGAAGGGAAGGAAAUCAUGUCAAGCGAAGCCUUGAAAAAGCUGCCCUGAGACGGUGUCCCGCCGAAAGUCUUUCAGCUCACAGCAGGAUGCUAAUCCAUGAAGGUGACCUCGCAGUACUGGUUAAUUAAGCUUUAUUGCUCACUGAAAAAGAAAAAAAAUCUAGCCAGAAUGUUGGCUCAAUUAAGAAACAUCAGGGAGAUAAAUUCAACCCAGUGUGUCUAAAAAUGACUACAAAACGAAGUUUGUUUGUGCGGUUGGUACCAUGUCGCUGUCUACGAGGGGAAGAGGAGACUGUCACUACUCUUGAUUAUUCUCAUUGCAGCUUAGAACAAGUUCCGAAAGAGAUUUUUACUUUUGAAAAAACCUUGGAGGAACUCUAUUUAGAUGCUAAUCAGAUUGAAGAGCUUCCAAAGCAACUUUUUAACUGUCAGUCUUUACACAAACUGAGUUUGCCAGACAAUGAUUUAACAACGUUACCAGCAUCCAUUGCAAACCUUAUUAAUCUCAGGGAACUGGAUGUCAGCAAGAAUGGAAUACAGGAGUUUCCAGAAAAUAUAAAAAAUUGUAAAGUUUUGACAAUUGUGGAGGCCAGUGUAAACCCUAUUUCCAAGCUCCCUGAUGGAUUUUCUCAGCUGUUAAACCUAACCCAGUUGUAUCUGAAUGAUGCUUUUCUUGAGUUCUUGCCAGCAAAUUUUGGCAGAUUAACUAAACUCCAAAUAUUAGAGCUUAGAGAAAACCAGUUAAAAAUGUUGCCUAAAACUAUGAAUAGACUGACCCAGCUGGAAAGACUGGAUUUGGGAAGUAACGAAUUCACGGAAGUGCCUGAAGUACUUGAGCAACUAAGUGGAUUGAAAGAGUUUUGGAUGGAUGCUAAUAGACUGACUUUUAUUCCAGGGUUUAUUGGUAGUUUGAAACAGCUCACAUAUUUGGAUGUUUCUAAAAAUAAUAUUGAAAUGGUUGAAGAAGGAAUUUCAACAUGUGAAAACCUUCAAGACCUCCUAUUAUCAAGCAAUUCACUUCAGCAGCUUCCUGAGACUAUUGGUUCGUUGAAGAAUAUAACAACGCUUAAAAUAGAUGAAAACCAGUUAAUGUAUCUGCCAGACUCUAUAGGAGGGUUAAUAUCAGUAGAAGAACUGGAUUGUAGUUUCAAUGAAGUUGAAGCUUUGCCUUCAUCUAUUGGGCAGCUUACUAACUUAAGAACUUUUGCUGCUGAUCAUAAUUACUUACAGCAGUUGCCCCCAGAGAUUGGAAGCUGGAAAAAUAUAACUGUGCUGUUUCUCCAUUCCAAUAAACUUGAGACACUUCCAGAGGAAAUGGGUGAUAUGCAAAAAUUAAAAGUCAUUAAUUUAAGUGAUAAUAGAUUAAAGAAUUUACCCUUUAGCUUUACAAAGCUACAGCAAUUGACAGCUAUGUGGCUCUCAGAUAAUCAGUCCAAACCCCUGAUACCUCUUCAAAAAGAAACUGAUUCAGAGACCCAGAAAAUGGUGCUUACCAACUACAUGUUCCCUCAACAGCCAAGGACUGAGGAUGUUAUGUUUAUAUCAGAUAAUGAAAGUUUUAACCCUUCAUUGUGGGAGGAACAGAGGAAACAGCGGGCUCAAGUUGCAUUUGAAUGUGAUGAAGACAAAGAUGAAAGGGAGGCACCUCCCAGGGAGGGAAAUUUAAAAAGAUAUCCAACACCAUACCCAGAUGAGCUUAAGAAUAUGGUCAAAACUGUUCAAACCAUUGUACAUAGAUUAAAAGAUGAAGAGACCAAUGAAGACUCAGGAAGAGAUUUGAAACCACAUGAAGAUCAACAAGAUAUAAAUAAAGAUGUGGGUGUGAAGACCUCAGAAAGUACUACUACAGUAAAAAGCAAAGUUGAUGAAAGAGAAAAAUAUAUGAUAGGAAACUCUGUACAGAAGAUCAGUGAACCUGAAGCUGAGAUUAGUCCUGGGAGUUUACCAGUGACUGCAAAUAUGAAAGCCUCUGAGAACUUGAAGCAUAUUGUUAACCAUGAUGAUGUUUUUGAGGAAUCUGAAGAACUUUCUUCUGAUGAAGAGAUGAAAAUGGCGGAGAUGCGACCACCAUUAAUUGAAACCUCUAUUAACCAGCCAAAAGUCGUAGCACUUAGUAAUAACAAAAAAGAUGAUACAAAGGAAACAGAUUCUUUAUCAGAUGAAGUUACACACAAUAGCAAUCAGAAUAACAGCAAUUGUUCUUCUCCAUCUCGGAUGUCUGAUUCAGUUUCUCUUAAUACUGAUAGUAGUCAAGACACCUCACUCUGCUCUCCAGUGAAACAAACUCAUAUUGAUAUUAAUUCCAAAAUCAGGCAAGAAGAUGAAAAUUUUAACAGCCUUUUACAAAAUGGAGAUAUUUUAAACAGUUCAACAGAGGAAAAGUUCAAAGCUCAUGAUAAAAAAGAUUUUAACUUACCUGAAUAUGAUUUGAAUGUUGAAGAGCGAUUAGUUCUAAUUGAGAAAAGUGUUGACUCAACAGCCACAGCUGAUGACACUCACAAAUUAGAUCAUAUCAAUAUGAAUCUUAAUAAACUUAUAACUAAUGAUACAUUUCAACCAGAGAUCAUGGAAAGAUCAAAAACACAGGAUAUUGUGCUUGGAACAAGCUUUUUAAGCAUUAAUUCUAAAGAGGAAACUGAGCACUUGGAAAAUGGAAACAAGUAUCCUAAUUUGGAAUCCGUAAAUAAGGUAAAUGGACAUUCUGAGGAAACUUCCCAGUCUCCUAAUAGGACUGAACCACAUGACAGUGAUUGUUCUGUUGACUUAGGUAUUUCCAAAAGCACUGAAGAUCUCUCCCCUCAGAAAAGUGGUCCAGUUGGAUCUGUUGUGAAAUCUCAUAGCAUAACUAAUAUGGAGAUUGGAGGGCUAAAAAUCUAUGAUAUUCUUAGUGAUAAUGGACCUCAGCAGCCAAGUACAACCGUUAAAAUCACAUCUGCUGUUGAUGGAAAAAAUAUAGUCAGGAGCAAGUCUGCCACACUGUUGUAUGAUCAACCAUUGCAGGUAUUUACUGGUUCUUCCUCAUCUUCUGAUUUAAUAUCAGGAACAAAGGCAAUUUUCAAGUUUGAUUCAAAUCAUAAUCCCGAAGAGCCAAAUAUAAUAAGAGGCCCCACAAGUGGCCCACAAUCUGCACCUCAAAUAUAUGGUCCUCCACAGUAUAAUAUCCAAUACAGUAGCAGUGCUGCAGUCAAAGACACUUUGUGGCACUCCAAACAAAAUCCCCAAAUAGACCAUGCCAGUUUUCCUCCUCAGCUCCUUCCUAGAUCAGAGAGCACAGAAAAUCAAAGUUAUGCUAAACAUUCUGCCAAUAUGAAUUUCUCUAAUCAUAACAAUGUUCGAGCUAAUACUGCAUACCAUUUACAUCAGAGACUUGGCCCAGCAAGACAUGGGGAAAUGUGGGCCAUCUCACCAAACGACCGACUUAUUCCUGCAGUAACUCGAAGUACAAUCCAGCGACAAAGUAGUGUGUCCUCCACAGCCUCUGUAAAUCUUGGUGAUCCAGGCUCUACAAGGCGGGCUCAGAUUCCUGAAGGAGAUUAUUUAUCAUACAGAGAGUUCCACUCAGCGGGAAGAACUCCUCCAAUGAUGCCAGGAUCACAGAGACCCCUUUCUGCACGAACAUACAGCAUAGAUGGUCCAAAUGCAUCAAGACCUCAGAGUGCUCGACCCUCUAUUAAUGAAAUACCAGAGAGAACUAUGUCAGUUAGUGAUUUCAAUUAUUCACGGACUAGUCCUUCAAAAAGACCAAAUGCAAGGGUUGGUUCUGAGCAUUCUUUAUUAGAUCCUCCAGGAAAAAGUAAAGUUCCUCGUGACUGGAGAGAACAAGUACUUCGACAUAUUGAAGCCAAAAAGUUAGAAAAGGUGUUUUUCUCUGGUACUGGGAAUAGAGUUCCAAAUUUAAACUCAGCCAGGACAAUUGGGAUGAUAAUGUGUGUUUCUAUCCUCUCCUUCACUCCCCACUGUUUCUAACAAAAAUGUAUUAAUUUUAUAUGUUUAUGUGUCUGUCUCUUUGAGAUUGUGCACACAUACUAAAAAUACACGUACCUCUGUUCAGCAUUUUCUGAACUUUGCUAUUAAUAAUUGUUGAUUAUCUAAAUUUAAAAAAUAGUUUACUAUAUAGUUAAGACAAUAACAAAAAAUGUAUUGCAAAUGUAAAUAUUUCAUCUAAUAUUUUUUCCCCAGUCCACAGUAUAUGAACUAACAUUGUCACUGACACAGAUGGCUUCUGGCAUGGCAUUUAUUCUUAACUUUUCUGAAUUUCUACAUUUCUGACCUACUUAAACUCAGUUAAGUGUUUCUGUGGCUCUAGUGUUGCUUAGCAAUAGUUGAUUAAAUAACUAAUGCUCGUGUUCAAUUUAUAAUUUUAUGUGUAGAUGUUCAUCUUUUGAAAGGAGUUAAAAAUGUAGAUACAGAUAUAUAUCCUUGUAAAACCAAUAUGAAUGCCAUAGUCAUAUGGCCCAAGUGUACAAGACAUGAUUUUUCUUUAAGAUUUAACUUUAUACUUACUCACUAGAUUUUACCCAAGCAUUAUCUUUCUUUCUUUAUUAAAUAUAAAAUGUGUUCUUAAAAACAGGUGAACAUACAACUUCAAUUAGCCAUUUUUAAAAAUUCCUUAAAUAAAAUUUUCAGAAAUGCCUAAAAUAUAUUAGUACCUCAUAUCAGUUUACAUGAAAUCUCAGCCUAUAAUUGUUCUUUUUAGUGCAGUCCUCAACUUUAAAUGAACUUUAAAUAGGUAAAUAUCCACAAGCAUUAGGCUACUUCAUUCUCAUCUAUGCAUUUUAUUUCAUCUAGUAACUCUGUACACACUGUUGAGGCUAUUUGAACUUUUGUGCUUUUUCUAAGGCACUUGGAAAUUUCUUAAGCAGAAGAGUAACAUAGGUGUGUUUUAUAAAUAAAUUUCUGGUGACGUUGUGGAACUAGAUUUUAGAGGAAGAGGCUGUAGUCAAAGAGAUUGAGUUAUGAUGCCGUUUAGUAAUCUAGAUAAGAAAUGAAAUGUGAACUUUUAUCAGUGCAGUUAAGACAAAUGAGUUCAAGAGAGAGCUCUGAAAUAGACUUUUAACAAGAGUUUACUUCUGAUUGAAUAUUCCUGUAAUCAAUCAGAAAGGAAAAGGGAUAAAGCUUGAGAUUGUGCCUUAAAUAACUGGUUGUUGGGAAUGUCUUUGGCUAUUAGUGGACAUAGAGGAGGAGUAGGAGAUUUGGAAGAAGAGAUGAGUUUGGUUUUUAUGUUCUGUGUAGUUUUCAUCUUAUAUGGCUGUUUUCCUACUCCUGUCUGACAGAUAUACCUGGAUUUCAGUACAUAAGAAGCAAGUAGUAACUAUCUCAUUGUUCAGUGUGCCAAUCCGCUUUUUUUUUUAAUUGCCUGAAAUAUUUACAUAUUUUGAAAUUCACGGUACGGGUUCUUGAAGAGUAUAUGACAGUAGUUUCCUAGUUGUUUUCACUAGUAAUUUAGAGGUGUGAAUUAGUUGAUUGAAACUAAAGAGAAGCCUUAUGAGAAAAGAAACAGGGCAAACUGUGUCUGAACACAAAUCUGCACCUGAUAACUCCCAUUUUCAAGGAUAUCAUACUUUGAAGUUACGAGGGGUGCUUGUUCUCUCAUCAUUUGCUUGCCCAGACUCCUGCCUUCCAGACCACUAGUUGACUACACUGUAGUAUCUUCUAGCUCAUCAGUUGGGAAGCAUUUCUAGCAAAUACCAAAGUAUAUAUCCUGCCGUUACCAUAACUCUACUGCAUUCCUUUUAGGAUAUUUUAUUCUCCAUGUCUUUCUUAAAUGUAUGCUGUGUUUGCCUGUUUCAGUUCUUAAAAAGUAUUCACAUGUGAGACUGCUUUUACCUAACAUACGUGAAACUUUUAUCUUAAAUGGAUUCAUGUUUUAUAAACCACAUUUUUAAAAGAAUUUAAAUUUUUAAAGAAUUACUUUCAAAAAAAUUUUUUAAAAAGCAUUUAGAGAGAAUUUUAGUCUUAACAGUUCCGAAUCCUAGCUGUGCUGCUCAGUUAGCUACUUGGACAAAUAACUUUGACUUUCCUUACCUUGGUGGAUUCAUGUGUAUGUUAGGUGCAAUGAAAGGAACUACUAGGAUUGUUUAAAAAUUAGAUGGGUUAAUACAUGCAAAGCACUUAGAAGGGUACCUGACACAUAUAACUAACUGCUAAAUAAGUGUUUAUUGCUAUUAUCUUCAUCCUCAUCAUCACCAUCUUUUAAAUACAAAGAAAUUAUCAGCUGAUUAAAGUUAUUUUUUUAAAACAGCAGAAUAUUGUGCAAUAGGUUAUUUUAUGAUGGUAAAAUAAUUAUUUUUCUUAAAAAUUUAUAGUUCAUAAUUUUAAAAUAUAAACAGAUUUCAUACAUCAAAGAUUAAGGCUUUUUUUAUUAUUAUACUUUAAGUUUUAGGAUACAUGUGCACAACGUGCAGGUUUGUUUCAUAUGUAUACAUGUGCCAUGUUGGUGUGCUGCACCCAUUAACUCGUCAUUUAGCAUUAGGUAUAUCUCCUAAUGCUAUCCCUCCCCCCUCCCCCGACCCCACAACAGUCCCCAGUGUGUGAUGUUCCCCUUCCUGUGUCCAUCUGUUCUCAUUGUUCAAUUUCCACCUGUGAGUGAGAACAUGCGGUGUUUGGUUUUUCGUCCUUGUGAUAGUUUGCUGAGAAUGAUGGUUUCCAGCUUCAUCCAUGUCCCUACAAAGGACAUGAACUUAUCAUUUUUUAUGGCUGCAUAGUAUUCACAUUUUCUUAAUCCAGUCUAUCAUUGUUGGACAUUUGCGUUGGUUCCAAGUCUUUGCUAUUGUGAAGAGUGCCACAAUAAACAUACGUGUGCAUGUGUCUUAAUAGCAGCAUGAUUUAUAAUCCUUUAGGUAUAUACCCAGUAAUGGGAUUGCUGGGUCAAAUGGUAUUUCUAGUUCUAGAUCCCUGAGGAAUCGCCACACUGACUUCCACAAUGGUUGAACUAGUUUACAGUCCCACCAACAGUGUAAAAGUGUUCCUAUUUCUCCACAUCCUCUCCAGCACCUGUUGUUUCCUGACUUUUUAAUGAUUGCCAUUCUAACUGGUGUGAGAUGGUAUCUAUCUCAUUGUGGUUUUGAUUUGUAUUUCUCUGAUGGCCAGUGAUGAUGAGCACUUUUUCAUGUGUUUUUUGGCUGCAUAAGUGUCUUCUUUUGAGAAGUGUCUGUUCAUAUGCUUUGCCUACUUUUUGAUGGGGUUGUUUUUUUCUUGUAAAUUUGUUUGAGUUCAUUGUAGAUUCUGGAUAUUAGCCCUUUGUCAGAUGAGUAGGUUGCAAAAAUUUUCUCCCGUUCUGUAGGUUGCCUGUUCACUCUGAUGGUGGUUUCUUUUGCUGUGCAGAAGCUCUUUAGUUUAAUUAGAUCCCAUUUGUCAAUUUUGGCUUUUGUUGCCAUUGCUUUUGGUGUUUUAGACAUGAAGUCCUUGCCCAUGCCUAUGUCCUGAAUGGUAUUGCCUAGGUUUUCUUCUAGGGUUUUUAUGGUUUUAGGUCUAACGUUUAAGUCUUUAAUGCAUCUUGAAUUAAUUUUAGUAUAAGGUGUAAGGAAGGGAUCCAGUUUCAGCUUUCUCCAUAUGGCUAGCCAGUUUUCCCAGCACCAUUUAUUAAAUAGGGAAUCCUUUCCCCAUUUCUUGUUUUUGUCAGGUUUGUCAAAGAUCAGAUAGUUGUAGAUAUGCGGCAUUAUUUCUGAGGGCUCUGUUCUGUUCCAUUGGUCUAUAUCCCUGUUUUGGUACCAGUACCGUGCCGUUUUGGUUACUGUAGCCUUGUAGUGUAGUUUGAAGUCAGGUAGCGUGAUGCCUCCAGCUUUGUUUUUUUUGGCUUAGGAUUGUCUUGGCAAUGCAGGCUCUUUUUUGGUUCCAUAUGAACUUUAAAGUAGUUUUUUCCAAUUCUGUGAAGAGAGUCAUUGGUAGCUUGAUGGGGAUGGCAUUGAAUCUAUAAAUUACCUUGGGCAGUAUGGCCAUUUUCAUGAUAUUGAUUCUUCCUACCCAUGAGUAUGAGAUGUUCUUCCAUUUGUUUGUAUCCUCUUUUAUUUCAUUGAGCAGUGGUUUGUAGUUCUCCUUGAAGAGGUCCUUCACAUCCCUUGUAAGUUGGAUUCCUAGGUGUUUUAUUCUCUUUGAAGCAAUUGUGAAUGGGAGUUCACUCAUGAUUUGGCUCUCUGUUUGUCUGUUAUUGGUGUAUAAGGAUGCUUGUGAUUUUUACACAUUGAUUUUAUAUCCUGAGACUUUGCUGAAGUUGCUUAUCAGCUUAAGGAGAUUUUGGGCUGAGAUGAUAGGGUUUUCUAGAUAUACAAUCAUGUCAUGUGCAAACAGGGACAAUUUGACUUCCUCUUUUCCUAAUUGAAUACCCUUUAUUUCCUUCUCCUGCCUGAUUACCCUGGCCAGAAUUUCCAACACUAUGUUGAAUAGGAGUGGUGAGAGAGGGCAUCCCUGUCUUGUGCCAGUUUUCAAAGGGAAUGCUUCCAGUUUUUGUCCAUUCAGUAUGAUAUUGGCUGUGGGUUUGUCAUAGACAGCUCUUACUAUUUUGAGAUACGUCCCAUCAGUACCUAAUUUAUUGAGAGUUUUUACCAUGAAGGGUUGUUGAAUUUUGUCAAAGGCUUUUUCUGCACCUAUUGAGAUAAUGAUGUGGUUUUUGUCUUUGGUUCUGUUUAUAUGCUGGAUUACGUUUAUUGAUUUUCAUAUGUUGAACCAGCCUUGCAUCCCAGGGAUGAAGCCCACUUGAUCAUGGUGGAUAAGCUUUUUGAUGUGUUGCUGGAUUCAGUUUGCCAGUAUUUUAUUGAGGAUUUUUGCAUCAAUGUUCAUCAAGGAUAUUGGUCUAAAAUUCUCUUUUUUGGUUGUGUCUCUGCCUGGCUUUCGUAUCAGGAUGAUGCUGGCCUCAUAAAAUGAGUUAGGGAGGAUUCCCUCUUUUUCUGUUGACUGGAAUAGUUUCAGAAGGAAUGGUACCAGCUCCUCCUUGUAACUCUGGUAGAAUUCAGCUGUGAAUCCAUGUGGUCCUGGACUUUUUUUGGUUGGUAAGCUAUUAAUUAUUGCCUCAAUUUCAGAGCCUGUUAUUGGUCUAUUCAGAGAUUCAACUUCUUCCUGGUUUAGUCUUGGGAGAGUGUUAUGUGUCAAGGAAUUUAUCCAUUUCUUCUAGAUUUUCUAGUUUAUUUGCGUAGAGGUGUUUUUAGUUUUCUCUGAUGGUAGUUUGUAUUUCUGUGGGAUUGGUGGUGAUAUGCCCUUUGUCAUUUUUUAUUGCGUCUGUUUGAUUCUUCUCUCUUUUCUUCUUUAUUAGUCUUGCUAGCAGUCUAUCAAUUCUGUUGAUCCUUUCAAAAAACCAGCUCCUGGAUUCAUUAAUUUUUUGAAGGGUUUUUUGUGUCUCUAUCUCCUUCAGUUCUGCUCUGAUCUUAGUUAUUUCUUGUCUUCUGCUAGUUUUUGAAUGUGUUUGCUCUUGCUUCUCUAGUGCUUUUAAUUGUGAUGUUAGGGUGUCAAUUUUAGAUCUUUCCUGCUUUCUCUUGUGGGCAUUUAGUGCUAUAAAUUUCCUUCUACACACUGCUUUGAAUGUGUCCCAGAGAUUCUGGUAUGUUGUGUCUUUAUUCUCAUUGGUUUCAAAGAACAUCUUUUUUUUCUACCUUCAUUUCGUUAGGUACCCAGUAGUCAUUCAGGAGCAGGUUGUGCAGUUUCGAUGUAGUUGAGCGGUUUUGAGUGAGUUUCUUAAUCCUGAGUUCUAGUUUGAUUGCACUGUGGUCUGAGAGACAGUUUGUUAUAAUUUCUGUUCUUUUAUAUUUGCUGAGGAGUGCUUGCUUUACUUCCAACUGUGUGGUCAAUUUUGGAAUAGGUGUGGUGUGGUGCUGAAAAGAAUGUAUAUUCUGUUGAUUUGGGGUGGAGAGUUCUGUAGAUGUCUGUUAGGUCUGCUUGGUGCAGAGCUGAGUUGAGUUCCUGGAUAUCCUUGUUAACUUUCUGUCUUGUUGAUCUGUCUAAUGUUGACAGUGGGGUGUUAAAGUCUCCCAUUAUUAUUGUGUGGGAGCCUAAGUCUCUUUGUAGGUCCCUAAGGACUUGCUUUAUGAAUCUGGGUGCUCCUGUAUUGGGUGCAUAUAUAUUUAGGAUAGUUAGUUCUUGUUGAAUUGAUCCCUUUACCAUUAUGUAAUGGCCUUCUUUGACUCUUUUGAUCUUUGUUGGUUUAAAGUCUGUUUUAUCGGAGACUAGGAUUGCAACCCCUGCCUUUUUUUUGUUUUCCAUUUGCUUGGUAGAUCUUCCUCCAUCCGUUUGUUUUGAGCCUAUGUGUGUCCUUGCAUGUGAGAUGGGUUUCCUGAAUACAGCACACUGAUGGGUCUUGCCUCUUUAUCCAAUUUGCCAGUCUGUGCCUUUUAAUUGGAGCAUUUAGCCCAUUUACAUUUAAGGUUAGUAGUGUUAUGUGUGAAUUUGAUCCUGUCAUUAUGAUGUUAGCUGGUUAUUUUGCUCAUUAGUUGAUGCAGUUUCUUCCUAGCCUUGAUGGUCUUUACAAUUUGGCAUGUUUUUGCAGUGGCUGGUACCGGUUGUUCCUUUCCAUGUUUAGUGCUUCCUUCAGGAGCUCUUUUAGGGCAGGCCUGGUGGUGACAAAAUCUCUCAGCAUUUGCUUGUCUGUAAGGUAUUUUAUUUCUCCUUCACUUAUGAAGCUUAGUUUGGCUGGAUAUGAAAUUCUGGGUUGAAAAUUCUUUUCUUUAAGAAUGUUGGAUAUUGGCCCCCACUCUCUUCUGGCUUGUAGAGUUUCUGCCAAGAGAUCAGCUGUUAGUCUGAUGGGCUUCCCUUUUUGGGUAACCCAACCUUUCUCUCUGGCUGCCCUUAACAUUUUUUCCUUCAUUUCAACUUUGGUGAAUCUGACAAUUAUGUGUCUUGGAGUUGCUCUUCUCGAGGAGUAUCUUUGUGGCGUUCUCUGUAUUUCCUGAAUUUGAAUGUUGGCUUGCCUUGCUAGAUUUGGUUAGUUCUCCUGGAUAAUAUCCUGCAGUGUUUUCCAACUUGGUUCCAUUCUCCCCGUCACUUUCAGGUACACCAGUGAGACGUAGAUUUGGUCUUUUCACAUAGUCCCAUAUUUCUUGGAGGCUUUGUUCGUUUCUUUUUAUUCUUUUUUCUCUAAACUUCUCUUCACGCUUCAUUUCAUUCAUUUCGUCUUCCAUCGCUGAUACCCUUUCUUCCAGUUGAUCGCAUCAGUUACUGAGGCUUGUGCAUUCGUCACAUAGUUCUCGUGCUGUGGUUUUCAGCUCCAUCGGGUCCUUUAAGGACUUCUCUGCAUUGGUUAUUCUAGUUAUCCAUUAGUCUAAUUUUUUUUCAAAGUUUUUAACUUCUUUGCCAUUGGUUUGAACUUCCUCCUUUAGCUCGGAGUAGUUUGAUCUUCUGAAGCCUUCCUCUCUCAACUCAUCAAAGUCAUUCUCCGUCCAGCUUUGUUCCGUUGCUGGUGAGGAGCUGCGUUCCUCUGGAGGAGGAGAGGUGUUCUGAUUUGUAGUUUCUGGUUUUUCUGCUCUGUUUUUUCCCCAUCUUUGUGGUUUUAUCUACCUUUGGUCUUUGAUGAUGGUGAUGUACAGAUGGGUUUUUGGUGUGGAUGUCCUUUCUGUUUGUUAGUUUUCCUUCUAAUAGUCACAACCCUCAGCUGCAGGUCUGUUGGAGUUGACUGGAGGUCCACUCCAGACCCUGUUUGCCUGGGUAUCAGCAGCACUGGCUGCAGAACAGCGGAUAUUGGUGAACCGCAAAUGCUGCUGCCUGAUCAUUCCUCUGGAAGUUUUGUCUCAGAGGAGUACCUGGCCGUGUGAGGUGUCAGUCUGCCCCUACUGGGGGGUGCCUCCCAGUUAGGCUACUUGAGGGUCAGGGACCCACUUGAGGAGGCAGUCUGCCUGUUCUCAGAUCUCAAGCUGCGUGCUGGGAGAACCACUACUCUCUUCAAAACUGUCAGACAGGGACAUUUAAGUCUGCAGAGGUUAUUGCUGUCUUUUGUUUGUCUGUGCCCUGCCCCCAGAGGUGGAGCCUACCGAGGCACGCAGGCCUCCUUGAGCUGUGGUGGGCUUCACCCAGUUCGAGCUUCCCAGCUGCUUUGGUUACCUACUCAAGCCUGGGCAAUGGCGGGUGCCCCUCCCCCAGCCUCGCUGUGGCCUUGCAGUUUGAUCUCAGACUGCUGUGCUAGCAAUGAGCGAGGCUCCAUGGGCGUAGGACCCUCCGAGCCAGUUGCGGGAUAUAAUCUCCUGGUGUGCGGUUUGUUAAGCCCGUUGGAAAAGCGCAGUAUUAGGGCAGGAGUGACCCGAUUUUCCAGGUGCCAUCUGUCACCCCUUCCUUUGACUAGGAAAGGGAAUUCCUUGACCCCUUGUGUUUUCCAGGUGAGGCGAUGCCUCACCCUGCUUCGGCUCAGGCAUGGUGUGCUGCACCCACUGUUCUGCACCCACUGUCCGGCACUCCCCAGUGAGAUGAACCCGGUACCUCAGUUGGAAGUGCAGAAAACACCCGUCUUCUGCGUCGCUCACGCUGGGAGCUGUAGACUGGACCUGUUCCUAUUCGGCCAUCUUGGCUCCUCCCAAUUUCUCGAUUAAGACAUUUUUAAAAAGUGAAGAUAGUCUCUGUAUGUUUAGCUUGUAAAAAUUUGUUUUAAAUACCUAUUUAUCAAGGAUGAUGAUCUUGAAUAAUUUUCUGUUAAAUAUACUUAUCUGUCAGAAACAAUACCAAUAAAAUGUCAAUAGAGACAUUCGUAUUUAUAUACACACUUAUAUACGUACACACAUAAAACUAACAAAAAUAGAAAUUUCAAUGGAAAUUUGGUAUUUUCUUCAUGAUUUCAUUAUUAAUCAUCUCUUCUUCAGAAAAUAUAGUUCAGAAGAUUAUUUCAUAGUUUAGGUAAUAACUGGUUCAAAAGAUGAAAUGUUAAUGUACUGCUAGUAAUUAUCUGUCGGUGAGAUUUGGGGACUUUUUGAUACAUUUCUAAAAUGUUUUCAUUUUGAAAGAUAAAAUGGUAAUGAUAAAUGCAAUAGUAAUCACAGAAGAUGGGAUUAUUCAACAAACAGUGCUUUUUGAAAAACUUACAAUUUUGAUAAAUAGGAUUAAGAUUAAUAGAUUAAGGUAAAAGUUAUAUAUCAAGAAGGAAUUCUGAAAGCAGAGACAAGGAGUUCAACCUGGUUGAAUUAAAGAUGUAUUUUGAGAACAUUUGAUAAUAAAGUAUGAAUAUUAGAAAGUCAUAAUAUAUAAAGUUUAUUUGGUAUUUACAAAGUGCCAGAAACUACUAUCACUGUACAGUUACCUUGCUAUACAAAUAUUUCUCAAUUUUCACAUGAGUCCUGUGUGAUAUUUUUAUUAUCUCAUUUUACCAUAAGGAAAUUUAGGCACAGAAGAGUUAAGUAAUUUUCCCAGGAUGAUAUGUGUUACGUAGUGUAGAGGAAUGACUUUAAAAGCCUAUCAGAAGAAUUUCAAGUUGACACAAUAAACAAAAGAGAGCCACUAUUAUUUCCUGAGCAUAUAGAGUAUUUUAGGAUAUCUUAGGCAAAAGUGUUCAGGAUGAAUUGAUAAGAAGUAGCUUAGGAAACAGUUUCAAUAAUAAAACAGCCAAAUGAGAGAUACUUGAGCUGGGGUUUUGGCUCUCGUGGUGAUGAGUCUGAAAAACACUUGGGUUAAAAUUGUUUAGUUUUAGGGAUGGAAUGAGAAAAAAGAUUGAAGAGGUAGCCAAGGUUUCUGAUUUGAGAUAUUUGGUCAUUAACCUUAUUUAAUUAAUUAAUUUUUUAAAUAGAGACAGGGUCUCACUAUGUUGCCCAGGCUGGUCUCAAACUCCUGGCCUCAAGCAAUCCUCUUGCUUCAGCCUCUCAAAGUGCUGUGAUUACAGAUGUGAGCCACCAUGCCCUGCCAAAUCAAUAUUUUUUUAAAGUUCUGGUAGUUAAGGAAAUGAAGUCUUUAAAGCAUUGUGGUAUAGUAUAAAAGUUUGGCAAAAAAUAGCUUAGUUGGUUUUGAAUAUAUUGAAUUUGAUGUGAUGACUGUGUGCAAGUAACAUGGAACACAAUACGAUACUAGGUUUAGUGAUGCAAAUUUGAGAUACAAACCAUGUGAAUGAGUGAAUUUUCCUAGGCAGUAAUUAUGUGGGAUAAGAAAAAAGUGUGUUUUUAAGAGACUGAAAAGAUACAUUGUUUUAAGUAAUGUUAAAUUGCUAAGAUUGCUAGACAUACUUAUUAUUUCAAAGAGCAGCCCAUUCCAAUUCAGUGAUAUGUACACCCUUAAGAUUUCUUCACCAUCUUUCAUCUUUUCCCCUCUUACCCACCAUUAACUGCUAGAAAUUUAUUAUUUUAAGGCAGGAUGGUUUGAAUAACCAAACAUUUGUACCUAGAUUUUACCUUUGUUCUUCCUUUAACCUAGGUAAGUGGUUUUCAAACUUUACUAUAUGGGGUCUAUAAAUAAAACUGUACAUUCCGAGUGAUUUCAGAGAUUUUCAGAUUAAUUUUGACCUGUGUGUGUGUGUGUGUGUGUGUGUGUGUGUGUGUGUGUGUGUGUGUGUGUGUGUGUGUGUGUGUGUGUUUUGCUUUGUAUGUGAACCAGCAUCCAUUUAUUUGUUAUCCCAUUUUCCAGUAAGGAAAUUCAGGCGCAGAAUAAUUAAGUAAUUUUCCCAGGAUGAUAUAUAUGUUAUGUGAAGGAGGGGGAACAACUUUAAAAGCUGGUCUGAAGAAUUUCAAGUUGACACAAUAAAUAAGGUGAAGCCACUGUUACUUCCUGAGCAGAUAUAGUACUUUAGGUUAUAUAAUGUUAGAUGUGGUUCUUUUGAGUUGUCUGAGAGUUUAAUGUGAUUCUACCACCAGCCUCCUAAAAAUAAUUUUAUUCAGUAAAAAUAAUCCUUAAUAUUGAAGCAUAAUUUGAGUAAUUUGCCAGUGAAAAUUAACUCUUUAUUUCUGCAAGUCUCUCGUGGGGAUGCUUUCUUUUCCUAUGUUCAAAACAUUCUAAAAUCAUGUAAUUCUGAAAAUUGUCCCUGUUUUAUUUAUAUAACAACUUUGUGCUACUUUGAUGCUUAUUCAUUAGAUGGUGUAAUCAGAAUGUAUGGGCGUUAGAAGCAGAUUGAAAGUGCUACAUAAAUAUAUUACUAAUUAACUACUUUAAUAGCAGCAGGAUUUAGACUCCAAACUUCAUUGAUUCAAAGUGGUAGAAGAUGAUGGAGGAUCUCUAUUCACUCCCCUACACCCACCAUCUUAAUUCUAAUGGCAAAGUAGACAUUUAAAAAUUUUACCCUGGGGGCUUUCACAGUGCCUGCCCUACCUCAUGAGGUCAGUUCCCAAAUUAAAAUUUGCUACUUUACUCAGCUGAGAGUUAGUAGUAAUAAUCUAUUGAAGCUUAAGUAGUUUUUAAACCUUUUAAUAGUCACCCCUCUUAACCUCCCACUGCCAAAAAUAAAAAAAAAAAAACAAAAAAAACUGUACCUGGAAUUCAAAGAUACAAAGUAGAUGUCACCUUGAAAAUUUCAAGAUUUAUUUAAUUAAUAAGCAAAAUUUGAAAAGGAAUAAGAACUUUUUAUUUCAGAGGUGAAUGGUUACUAUCAGCAUUUACUAACAUUCCUUAUGAGAACUCAGAUAUUAAGCAUUCCAAACCAUAAUAUGAUUAACACAACAUGGUAAGUGUUACGUUCACUCGUUAUUAUACAACUAUCAGUAUGUAAUGAACAACAUUGCCCAGGACAUUAUGCCUAGCAUUUAAUUGAGCACUCUACAAUGUGUUGUGACAGGAAGCAGUUUUACGUGGAUGUCUGCACAAACCUGAAUUUAAAACCAGACCUGUUUUGAGCUUCAGCUUUAUUCAUCAGUAAAAUAUUUACAGUAAGCUCAUGUGUUUGGAGAUGACAGAGAAAGCUUUGCUACAAGAUCUGUCUAAAGGGUUAAUCAGGCCACUUGAGUCAAUAACACAUUAAAGCUCUCUGCACAGCAAA